GCGGAGGCUUGGGGCAGCCGGGUAGCUCGGAGGUCGUGGCGCUGGGGGCUAGCACCAGCGCUCUGUCGGGAGGCGCAGCGGUUAGGUGGACCGGUCAGCGGACUCACCGGCCAGGGCGCUCGGUGCUGGAAUUUGAUAUUCAUUGAUCCGGGUUUUAUCCCUCUUCUUUUUUCUUAAACAUUUUUUUUUAAAACUGUAUUGUUUCUCGUUUUAAUUUAUUUUUGCUUGCCAUUCCCCACUUGAAUCGGGCCGACGGCUUGGGGAGAUUGCUCUACUUCCCCAAAUCACUGUGGAUUUUGGAAACCAGCAGAAAGAGGAAAGAGGUAGCAAGAGCUCCAGAGAGAAGUCGAGGAAGAGAGAGACGGGGUCAGAGAGAGCGCGCGGGCGUGCGAGCAGCGAAAGCGACAGGGGCAAAGUGAGUGACCUGCUUUUGGGGGUGACCGCCGGAGCGCGGCGUGAGCCCUCCCCCUUGGGAUCCCGCAGCUGACCAGUCGCGCUGACGGACAGACAGACAGACACCGCCCCCAGCCCCAGCUACCACCUCCUCCCCGGCCGGCGGCGGACAGUGGACGCGGCGGCGAGCCGCGGGCAGGGGCCGGAGCCCGCGCCCGGAGGCGGGGUGGAGGGGGUCGGGGCUCGCGGCGUCGCACUGAAACUUUUCGUCCAACUUCUGGGCUGUUCUCGCUUCGGAGGAGCCGUGGUCCGCGCGGGGGAAGCCGAGCCGAGCGGAGCCGCGAGAAGUGCUAGCUCGGGCCGGGAGGAGCCGCAGCCGGAGGAGGGGGAGGAGGAAGAAGAGAAGGAAGAGGAGAGGGGGCCGCAGUGGCGACUCGGCGCUCGGAAGCCGGGCUCAUGGACGGGUGAGGCGGCGGUGUGCGCAGACAGUGCUCCAGCCGCGCGCGCUCCCCAGGCCCUGGCCCGGGCCUCGGGCCGGGGAGGAAGAGUAGCUCGCCGAGGCGCCGAGGAGAGCGGGCCGCCCCACAGCCCGAGCCGGAGAGGGAGCGCGAGCCGCGCCGGCCCCGGUCGGGCCUCCGAAACCAUGAACUUUCUGCUGUCUUGGGUGCAUUGGAGCCUUGCCUUGCUGCUCUACCUCCACCAUGCCAAGUGGUCCCAGGCUGCACCCAUGGCAGAAGGAGGAGGGCAGAAUCAUCACGAAGUGGUGAAGUUCAUGGAUGUCUAUCAGCGCAGCUACUGCCAUCCAAUCGAGACCCUGGUGGACAUCUUCCAGGAGUACCCUGAUGAGAUCGAGUACAUCUUCAAGCCAUCCUGUGUGCCCCUGAUGCGAUGCGGGGGCUGCUGCAAUGACGAGGGCCUGGAGUGUGUGCCCACUGAGGAGUCCAACAUCACCAUGCAGAUUAUGCGGAUCAAACCUCACCAAGGCCAGCACAUAGGAGAGAUGAGCUUCCUACAGCACAACAAAUGUGAAUGCAGACCAAAGAAAGAUAGAGCAAGACAAGAAAAAAAAUCAGUUCGAGGAAAGGGAAAGGGGCAAAAACGAAAGCGCAAGAAAUCCCGGUAUAAGUCCUGGAGCGUGUACGUUGGUGCCCGCUGCUGUCUAAUGCCCUGGAGCCUCCCUGGCCCCCAUCCCUGUGGGCCUUGCUCAGAGCGGAGAAAGCAUUUGUUUGUACAAGAUCCGCAGACGUGUAAAUGUUCCUGCAAAAACACAGACUCGCGUUGCAAGGCGAGGCAGCUUGAGUUAAACGAACGUACUUGCAGAUGUGACAAGCCGAGGCGGUGAGCCGGGCAGGAGGAAGGAGCCUCCCUCAGGGUUUCGGGAACCAGAUCUCUCACCAGGAAAGACUGAUACAGAACGAUCGAUACAGAAACCACGCUGCCGCCACCACACCAUCACCAUCGACAGAACAGUCCUUAAUCCAGAAACCUGAAAUGAAGGAAGAGGAGACUCUGCGCAGAGCACUUUGGGUCCGGAGGGCGAGACUCCGGCGGAAGCAUUCCCGGGCGGGUGACCCAGCACGGUCCCUCUUGGAAUUGGAUUCGCCAUUUUAUUUUUCUUGCUGCUAAAUCACCGAGCCCGGAAGAUUAGAGAGUUUUAUUUCUGGGAUUCCUGUAGACACACCCACCCACAUACAUACAUUUAUAUAUAUAUAUAUUAUAUAUAUAUAAAAAUAAAUAUCUCUAUUUUAUAUAUAUAAAAUAUAUAUAUUCUUUUUUUAAAUUAACAGUGCUAAUGUUAUUGGUGUCUUCACUGGAUGUAUUUGACUGCUGUGGACUUGAGUUGGGAGGGGAAUGUUCCCACUCAGAUCCUGACAGGGAAGAGGAGGAGAUGAGAGACUCUGGCAUGAUCUUUUUUUUGUCCCACUUGGUGGGGCCAGGGUCCUCUCCCCUGCCCAGGAAUGUGCAAGGCCAGGGCAUGGGGGCAAAUAUGACCCAGUUUUGGGAACACCGACAAACCCAGCCCUGGCGCUGAGCCUCUCUACCCCAGGUCAGACGGACAGAAAGACAGAUCACAGGUACAGGGAUGAGGACACCGGCUCUGACCAGGAGUUUGGGGAGCUUCAGGACAUUGCUGUGCUUUGGGGAUUCCCUCCACAUGCUGCACGCGCAUCUCGCCCCCAGGGGCACUGCCUGGAAGAUUCAGGAGCCUGGGCGGCCUUCGCUUACUCUCACCUGCUUCUGAGUUGCCCAGGAGACCACUGGCAGAUGUCCCGGCGAAGAGAAGAGACACAUUGUUGGAAGAAGCAGCCCAUGACAGCUCCCCUUCCUGGGACUCGCCCUCAUCCUCUUCCUGCUCCCCUUCCUGGGGUGCAGCCUAAAAGGACCUAUGUCCUCACACCAUUGAAACCACUAGUUCUGUCCCCCCAGGAGACCUGGUUGUGUGUGUGUGAGUGGUUGACCUUCCUCCAUCCCCUGGUCCUUCCCUUCCCUUCCCGAGGCACAGAGAGACAGGGCAGGAUCCACGUGCCCAUUGUGGAGGCAGAGAAAAGAGAAAGUGUUUUAUAUACGGUACUUAUUUAAUAUCCCUUUUUAAUUAGAAAUUAAAACAGUUAAUUUAAUUAAAGAGUAGGGUUUUUUUUCAGUAUUCUUGGUUAAUAUUUAAUUUCAACUAUUUAUGAGAUGUAUCUUUUGCUCUCUCUUGCUCUCUUAUUUGUACCGGUUUUUGUAUAUAAAAUUCAUGUUUCCAAUCUCUCUCUCCCUGAUCGGUGACAGUCACUAGCUUAUCUUGAACAGAUAUUUAAUUUUGCUAACACUCAGCUCUGCCCUCCCCGAUCCCCUGGCUCCCCAGCACACAUUCCUUUGAAAUAAGGUUUCAAUAUACAUCUACAUACUAUAUAUAUAUUUGGCAACUUGUAUUUGUGUGUAUAUAUAUAUAUAUAUGUUUAUGUAUAUAUGUGAUUCUGAUAAAAUAGACAUUGCUAUUCUGUUUUUUAUAUGUAAAAACAAAACAAGAAAAAAUAGAGAAUUCUACAUACUAAAUCUCUCUCCUUUUUUAAUUUUAAUAUUUGUUAUCAUUUAUUUAUUGGUGCUACUGUUUAUCCGUAAUAAUUGUGGGGAAAAGAUAUUAACAUCACGUCUUUGUCUCUAGUGCAGUUUUUCGAGAUAUUCCGUAGUACAUAUUUAUUUUUAAACAACGACAAAGAAAUACAGAUAUAUCUUAAAAAAAAAAAAGCAUUUUGUAUUAAAGAAUUUAAUUCUGAUCUCAAA